GGGUGGCAAGAUGGUGGCGCGCAGGAGGAAGUGCGCCGCGCGGGACCCGGAGGACCGUAUCCCCAGCCCACUGGGCUACGCAGCUAUUCCAAUCAAGUUCUCUGAAAAGCAACAGGCUUCUCACUACCUCUAUGUGAGAGCACACGGCGUUCGACAAGGCACCAAGUCCACCUGGCCUCAGAAGAGGACUCUUUUUGUCCUCAAUGUGCCCCCAUACUGCACAGAGGAGAGCCUGUCCCGCCUCCUGUCCACCUGUGGCCUCGUCCAGUCUGUAGAGUUGCAGGAGAAGCCGGACCUGGCUGAGAGCCCAAAGGAGUCAAGGUCGAAGUUUUUUCAUCCCAAGCCAGUUCCGGGUUUCCAGGUAGCCUAUGUGGUGUUCCAGAAGCCAAGUGGGGUGUCAGCGGCCUUGGCCCUGAAGGGCCCCCUGCUGGUGUCCACAGAGAGCCACCCUGUGAAGAGUGGCAUUCACAAGUGGAUCAGUGACUACGCAGACUCUGUGCCCGACCCUGAGGCCCUGAGGGUGGAAGUGGACACGUUCAUGGAGGCAUAUGACCAGAAGAUCGCUGAGGAAGAAGCUAAGGCCAAGGAGGAGGAGGGGGUCCCUGACGAGGAGGGCUGGGUGAAGGUGACCCGCCGGGGCCGGCGGCCUGUGCUCCCCCGGACUGAGGCAGCCAGCUUGCGGGUGCUGGAGAGGGAGAGACGGAAGCGCAGCCGAAAAGAGCUGCUCAACUUCUACGCCUGGCAGCAUCGAGAGAGCAAGAUGGAGCAUCUAGCGCAGCUGCGCAAGAAGUUCGAGGAGGACAAGCAGAGGAUCGAGCUGCUGCGGGCCCAGCGCAAAUUCCGACCGUACUGAGCUGUGAGAGCCGCAGUGAAUGGCUGGAGGUGCAGGGCCAGGAGGAGGCGAGGCAGGGCCUGCAGCGGUCUCUGAGAGGCCGAGCUCUGGCCAACGGGCCCCAGGUUGAAGGCCACCGCGUCCAACAGCCCCAUCAGAGUCCACACAGGCCAGGAGGGAAGGACCAGGCCACCCCUCGGGUCUUGUGCUUCAGCAGUCCUGGGGACCCAGGCGUGCCGAGAGGAGGACUUGUCCUUCCUGCUUCUUGCCUCCACACCCUCCUCUCCAGGACCCUGGAUGAAUCCGUUCUGUGCUUCCUUUUCCCUCAAUGCAAAAGCCCUUGCUGGCAACGAAAAAGCCUCAAAAGCAGUGAGAAUACAAGAACCUUUUAUUUUCCAUCCAGUUGGGCAGCAGGGAAAGGCUAGGUGGGCCCAGCCCGCCCUUCCUUCCUCCAGCUGGCUGGAGAUUAUUAGCCAGGAGACAGCAGCCCUGGAACCCAGACUCUGUCUCCCCCUUGAGGUCACAGAUGUUGAAGUUGGAAUCUCGCUCCUUCCCCUGACUACCAUCCUAGGCUGGGCCUCAAGACUAGUGAGGCCUGUCCCCACCAUCCCUGGCCUUGUUGUGGGGCUCAGGAACUCAGAGUCCCAGUGUUGAGUCUGGGAGCACUAGGUCUUCAUAGUUCCAGGCCCAGAGCUACAGCUGGGCUGGGAGCGUGUGUGUGCACUGUAAGAAGGAGCUGAUGAUACUGGCCACGUGCUGGGGUUCGCUCAUGUGGACACAGUGAUUGCCUGGGACUUCCACAAACUGGAACCGCUGGAGAGGGGAGGGGGUGGGUAGUGAGAUGUGGCCAGAGGAGCCUAGGGAGCUCCAUGGGCCCCGGGGUCAGGGCCCUCCCACAGCAUUCCAGCUCCCUGCAGGUCAGGAGCGCCUCCCACAGUGAGUUUCCCCCACACUCGGCUCCUUGGAGCCCCGACAGUCCAUAGCACCCCAGGAGAUGUCUAACCUUAGGGACUUGGAGGCCUCCCAGGGGUCUAGGCCAGCUGAGUUGUGAAGUUGCAUGGCAGGGACAGGGCAGGGCCGAGGCCAGGGUUGCUGUGAUUGUAUCCGAAGUAGUCCUCGUGAGAAAAGAUAAUGAGAUGACGUGAGCAGCCUGCAGACUUGUGUCUGCCUUCAAGAAGCCAGACAGGAAGGCCCUGCCUGCCUUGGCUCUGACCUGGCGGCCAGCCAGCCAGCCACAGGUGGGCUUCUUCCUUUUGUGGUGACAACGCCAAGAAAACUGCAGAGGCCCCAGGGUCAGGUGUAAGUGGGUAGGUGACCAUAAAACACCAGGUGCUCCCAGGAACCCGGGCAAAGGCCAUCCCCACCUACAGCCAGCAUGCCCACUGGCGUGAUGGGUGCAGAGGGAUGAGGCAGCCAGGUGUUCUGCUGUGGUUUGGGAGCCUAUAAAGUGAGACUAGGCUGGGCAUGGUGGCUCCCAUCUGCAAAACCAGCACUUUGGGAGGCCAAGGUGGGCGGAUCGCCUGAGGUCAGGAGUUUGAGACCAGCCUGGCCAACAUGGUGAACCCCCAUCUCUUAAAAAUAUAAAAAUUAGCUGGGCAUGGUGGCAGGUGCCUGUAAUCCCAGCUACUCAGGAGGCUGAGGCACGAGAGUCGCUUGAACCCGGGAGGUGGAGGUUACAGUAAGCUGAGAUCUUCCCACUGCACUCCAGCCUGAGCGACAGAGUGAGACUCCAUCUCAAAAAAAAAAAAAAAGUGUGACUAUUAGCUGGGCAUGAUGGCAUGCGCCUGUAGUGCCACCUACUCAGGUGGCUGAGGUGGGAGGAUCAUUUGAGCCCAGGAGUUUGAGGCUGCAGUGAGCUAUGACUGAGCCUGAGCAACAGAAUGAGACCCUGUCUCUCAAAAAAUGUGGGACUGUCUCUGGCAGUUGGGUCACCUAAUUGUGCCUGGCCCCAAGAAGGAGGGGUGGGUACUUGAGGAUGGUAAAGAACCUCCCCACCAAAGGUCUCUGUUUCUUAAAUUCUGAUUACAUGUGUCCCCAGGCCUCUAGGGACUGAUCACUGGAGCAUGAGGCCUGAUAGAUCCUGGUGGUCACUUGUUGGGCCUGGGGGCAGACCAGGGGUCUUUCCCAGUGCAUGAGAAGAGAUGGGUGAGGUGGGACCAGAGUGGGCGACAGUGGCUGGACACCAGCUGCCUGAGCCCCGCCUUACCUCUUUGAGGGUGGAUUUCAUUGUGUCUAUCAUGAACGACAGGGACUCCUUGUCAGAGUAAUUCUCUCUUGGAUCAAAAUAUCCGUGGACUGCUCUGGAAAGUGAGGAGUUGGGGGUUGUUGGGGUUCAUCUUAGAACCGCCUCCCAGCGGUGCCCCCAUCCUGCCCUGGGUUCAGGCCUCUGAGGAGAAACCAAAGCCUGGGCUACCCCAACUCCCACAGCUGGGUCCCUUGACCCUGGGUUGGAUUUGAGGCUCAGUUAAUCUCAGCUCACGCUCAGCUGGCACAAGCCAGGCGCAAGCAAGUGCUGAAGGCACAGCCUUGCUGGGGCGCAGGGAGUUCAGGACUUGGUCACAGUCAGCCCUGAACAGCAGAGCUGGGAUCUGAACAGGCGCUGGAGCCCACACUUGCUCUGAGAGAGAAUUUAUGUCUUCACAAUCCUCCCAUUGAAAGUCUACAAUCCUGGCCGGGUAUGGUGGCUCACGCCUGUAAUCCCAGCACUUUGGGAGGCUGAGGCGGGUGGAUCACGAGGUCAGGAGAUGAGACCAUCCUGGCUAACAUGGUGAAACCCUGUCUGUACUAAAAAUACAAAAAUUAGCCGGGCUUGGUGGUGGGUGCCUGUAGUCCCAGCUACUCCGGAGGCUGAGGCAGGAGAAUGGCGUGAACCCGGGAGGCGGACCUUGCAGUGAGCUGAGAUUGCACCACUACACUCCAGCCUGGGCGACAGAGCCAGACUCCAUCUCAAAAAAAAAAAAAAAAAAGUCUACAAUCCCGUGGUUUUUAAUACAUUGAGUUGUGAGACCAUCGUCACAAUUACAUUUUCAUCACCCCCAAAGAAAUCGCAAACCUCUGAGCUUACACACACACACACACACCCCACCCCCCCACCCCCAACAGGCUUCCGGUCCUGAGCAACCAUGACCUGGCUUUGUCUCUGCCGUGUGUCCUAUUUGGACUUGAACGUGAAUGCAGCCAUACAACACGUAGACGGUUGUGUCUGACUUCAUCCACUUAGUGCGAUGUUUUCAAGGCUCAUCCAUGCUGGAGCCCAUGUCAGUGCUUCGUUUCUUUUUAUGGCUUAAAAAUCGUCUAUGGUGGGCCACGCACGGUGGCUCUCGCCUGUAAUCCCAACACUGGGAGGCCGAGGCAGGCGGAUCAUGAGGUCAGGAGAUGGAGAGCAGCCUGGCCAACAUGGCGAAACCUCGUCUCUACUAAAAAUACAAAAAUAAGCCAGGCGUGGUGGCGGGCGCCUGUAGUCCCAGCUACUCGGGAGGCUGAGGCAGGAGAAUCGUUUGAAUCCAGGAGGCAGAGGUUGCAGUGAGUCGAGACUGGGCUCACUGGUUAUGGAGCCUUACCUGGGCAUGCCCCCCGCUGACACCUGUGGAAAGGCAUGGGACAGCCCCGGCCCAUCCCCUGCUGCCUGAGCCCUCCCCUCCUCUGACCUUCCUCCUUCCAUGACCCUGCUGCCAGGGGGGCUUCCCAAAAAAGAUCUUGAGUCUUAGCGAUGUGGUCGACACGCAGAGAACUUGGAGCCUCAUGCCAGGGCCCCCUCCCAGAGAUUCCUGGCGCCCAUGUCUCCUUGGGGGGUGACUGAAGGGGAUGGGUCCAGACUCACUUGAUCAACAGGACAUGGGCCUGCAGCUUCCUGAUGGAAUGCGCACACAGCUCCCUGCUGACGAAGUCAAUGCUGUUCUCUGCCUGCAGAGACAAAAACAUGGUGAAUUCUCGUCACAAGGCACAGGCACUCUCGUGGGCACGAAACCCAUCUCUGUUGGGGUGGCUAAGCCCUGGCGAGGGCACCUUAGCCACCCACCCUGGGUCUGAGCCCAGGACCCCACAUCACUGCCUCAUCGAAGGCUCUUUAGCCCCUGGUGGCCAGAGACUCCUGCCCUCUCCAAGUCUGUUCUCCCCUCUUCCUGGGCUCGUGGCUACCCAGCCUGACUCCAUUUCCAAUACUCCUUUGCCACCAGGUAUGGCUGUGUGAUUAAAGUCAGAGAAGUGAGUUGGGCCACUUUUGGGCCUGGAUUUUAGGACUUAGGUGUGGCCCUUCCACACCCCUUUCCCAGUCCAUAGGCUGCACCUCACGCUGUCCCCUGCCAGCCUGGGACAGGCUUCUUGCCAGGAGAAAGAAACUUGCUGGGACCACAGUGCAGGAUGGGCACUCCGUGAUGGCCCCAGCCAGCCUCCUCCGCGGCCCUGCCUGCCCUGUCUUGUGACUGUUUUACGUCUGGAUGGCGGGGAUGUGGCCAGCUUGAGUGAGAUGUGCUGUAGGUGUGACACGAAGCUGGAUUUGGAAAACAGCAUGCAAAAUAAUGCAAUCAAGCUUUAUGUUGAUUACAUCUUAAAUCACAUUGUGGAUGUUAAAUAAAAAUAUGAGAAGAA